AUGCGCGCAAGAGAGCGGGAAGCCGAGCUGGGCGAGAAGUAGGGGAGGGCGGUGCUCCGCCGCGGUGGCGGUUGCUAUCGCUUCGCAGAACCUACUCAGGCAGCCAGCUGAGAAGAGUUGAGGGAAAGUGCUGCUGCUGGGUCUGCAGACGCGAUGGAUAACGUGCAGCCGAAAAUAAAACAUCGCCCCUUCUGCUUCAGUGUGAAAGGCCACGUGAAGAUGCUGCGGCUGGCACUAACUGUGACAUCUAUGACCUUUUUUAUCAUCGCACAAGCCCCUGAACCAUAUAUUGUUAUCACUGGAUUUGAAGUCACCGUUAUCUUAUUUUUCAUACUUUUAUAUGUACUCAGACUUGAUCGAUUAAUGAAGUGGUUAUUUUGGCCUUUGCUUGUGUUUGCACUUGUGACAGCAGUAUGCUGUCUUGCCGACGGGGCCCUUAUUUACCGGAAGCUUCUGUUCAAUCCCAGCGGUCCUUACCAGAAAAAGCCUGUGCAUGAAAAAAAAGAAGUUUUGUAAUUUUAUAUUACUUUUUAGUUUGAUACUAAGUAUUAAACAUAUUUCUGUAUUCUUCCACAUAUUUUCUGCAGUUAUUUUAACUCAGUAUAGGAGCUAGAGGAAGAGAUUUCCGAAGUCUGCACCCCGCGCAGAGCACUACUGUAACUUCCAAGGGAGCGCUGGGAGCAGCGGGAUCGGGUUUUCCGGCACCCGGGCCUGGGUGGCAGGGAAGAAUGUGCCGGGAUCCGCCUCAGGGAUCUUUGAAUCUCUUUACUGCCUGGCUGGCCGGCAGCUCCG